GGUGAUACAGAAGAAAAGACAGUCUCCAUUUUCAAACAGUCCCUCCUGGGAGAACACAGACAGGCAGAGGAUUACAACACAAGGCAGCAAGCACUGGGAGACGAAAGUUUUGGCAUCUGUUCCCUGGCUGUGCCAAGAUGGGCGAUUGGAGCUUCCUGGGAAAUUUCCUGGAGGAAGUACACAAGCACUCGACCGUGGUAGGCAAGGUCUGGCUCACUGUCCUCUUCAUAUUCCGUAUGCUCGUGCUGGGCACAGCUGCUGAGUCUUCCUGGGGGGAUGAGCAGGCUGAUUUCCGGUGUGAUACGAUUCAGCCUGGCUGCCAGAAUGUCUGCUACGACCAGGCUUUCCCCAUCUCCCACAUUCGCUACUGGGUGCUGCAGAUCAUCUUCGUCUCCACGCCCUCUCUGGUGUACAUGGGCCACGCCAUGCACACUGUGCGCAUGCAGGAGAAGCGCAAGCUACGGGAGGCCGAGAGGGCCAAAGAGGUCCGGGGCUCUGGCUCUUACGAGUACCCGGUGGCAGAGAAGGCAGAACUGUCCUGCUGGGAGGAAGGGAAUGGAAGGAUUGCCCUCCAGGGCACUCUGCUCAACACCUAUGUGUGCAGCAUCCUGAUCCGCACCACCAUGGAGGUGGGCUUCAUUGUGGGCCAGUACUUCAUCUACGGAAUCUUCCUGACCACCCUGCAUGUCUGCCGCAGGAGUCCCUGUCCCCACCCGGUCAACUGUUACGUAUCCCGGCCCACAGAGAAGAAUGUCUUCAUUGUCUUUAUGCUGGCUGUGGCUGCACUGUCCCUCCUCCUUAGCCUGGCUGAACUCUACCACCUGGGCUGGAAGAAGAUCAGACAGCGAUUUGUCAAACCGCGGCAGCACAUGGCUAAGUGCCAGCUUUCUGGCCCCUCUGUGGGCAUAGUCCAGAGCUGCACACCACCCCCCGACUUUAAUCAGUGCCUGGAGAAUGGCCCUGGGGGAAAAUUCUUCAAUCCCUUCAGCAAUAAUAUGGCCUCCCAACAAAACACAGACAACCUGGUCACCGAGCAAGUACGAGGUCAGGAGCAGACUCCUGGGGAAGGUUUCAUCCAGGUUCGUUAUGGCCAGAAGCCUGAGGUGCCCAAUGGAGUCUCACCAGGUCACCGCCUUCCCCAUGGCUAUCAUAGUGACAAGCGACGUCUUAGUAAGGCCAGCAGCAAGGCAAGGUCAGAUGACCUAUCAGUGUGACCCUCCUUUAUGGGAGGAUCAGGACCAGGUGGGAACAAAGGAGGCUCAGAGAGGAAAGACGUGUCCCUUCUGAACUGAUGCUUUCUCACUGUCAUCACUGCUUGGCUCCUUUGAGCCCCGGGUCUCAAUGACGUUGCUCAUUAAUUCUAGAAACUAUAACCAGGGCUCUGGGAUAGUAAGAGAGGUGACAACCCACCCAGACUGCAGUUCCCUCCCCACCCUCUACCCAGUAUACGAAGCCUUUCAGAUUACUCAUGAAACAGGGUAGAGGGAAAGAAGGGAAGCAUGGCAAAAGCUGGCCUGGAAGGGAUAGCCAGAGGGAUAGAAUGACUCUCUCUCUACAUACCAGCAGCAUACCAAAUGCGUUCUCUAAGUUCCUACCUCCUUGACCUGAUCACCCUCCCUCCUCCAAGGAAGAGCUCAAAGUUCCCAGCCAAUAGACAGCAUGAAUCAAGGAACUUGCAUUAUAUGUGCUCUUGAAUCUGUUGUCUCCAUGGACCAUUCCUCGGAGUAGUGGUGAGAUGGCCUUGGGUUGCCCUUGGCUUCUCCUCCCUCUACUCAGCCUUAAAAAGGGCUUCUUGGAACUUUACCAGCAGCCUCAGCUUUACAAAUGCCUUGGUAUGUACCUCUGGCAAAUGCCCUGGUAUGUACCUCUGGCAAAUGCCCCACCUUGGUGAUGUUGCAACCUUUCCUUCUGCUAGGGUGUACACCUAGCCUGUGCAGGUGUCAGCCCUGCUAGGGAGUCACUGUACACACAAACUCUACUGGAAUUCCUGCCAACAUCUGUCACCCUGCAGCUCCUUUACAGUUCAAUCCAAUGAUAGAAACCAUCCCUUCCCUUUCUCCCUUGGCUGUUCACCCAGCCAUUCCCUGAAGGCCUUACCAACAGGAAUAUCCAAGAAGCUGUUGUCCUCUCUCGAACCCUGACCAGAUCAUCAGCCACUGAGGCCAGUGGAAUUUCCCCAGGCCUUGUUAAAACAAAGAAAGCAUUGUACUUCUCAGAUUCCCCUUGUGGAAAAAAAAAUUCUGCUGUGAAGAUGAAAAUAAAAAUGGAGAGAAAACACUGGAAAACUAUUUUCCCCUCCUAUUUACUUCCUUUGCUGACUGCCAACUUAGUGCCAAGAGGAGGUGUGAUGACAGCUAUGGAGGCCCCCAGAUCUCUCUCUCCUGGAGGCUUUAGCAGGGGCAAGGAAAUAGUAGGGGAAUCUCCAGCUCUCUUGGCAGGGCCUUUAUUUAAAGAGCGCAGAGAUUCCUAUGUCUCCCUAGUGCCCCUAAUGAGACUGCCAAGUGGGGGCUGUAGAAAAGCCUUGCCUUCCCCAGGGAUUGGCCUGGUCUCUGUAUUCACUGGAUCCAUAAUGGGUUGCUGUUGUUUUGGAUGAAGGUAAACGAUGCUUGGAAUUGGAAACUGAGACUUAUAGAGGGAUUAUUACAUUAUUAAAAUGCACGUGUGUGUGUGUGUGGGUGCUGAUGGGAUGGGUAAAGGCUUGGGGAGUCCUGAAAUAAGGAAAGGAAACCACAGAGAAACUUGUGUCUUCCUGCUCUCCUCUCCGGCUGCCUGGCAGUUAUUAACCUAAACAGAUAGCCACAAGAGGUUGGGACAGAGGAGGGUAAAGGCUCAGAAGGAGGUUCAACCUCUGACUCACCUGCCCAUCUCUGGGCCCUCUGCUGACACUUGGAUGCUAUUGUUGGGUGGAAAGAUAAAUGAGAGUGGAGAGGUGGAGGAAAGUGACUAGGAUGCCAUUUAGGAAGGAAUGUCUGAUCAUCCCGGGUCCCUGGAGGGGACACCUUUUAAUCUAUUGCCUAGCAUUAAUAUUUUCUCUCCUUCUAUCUCUGAAAUGUUUUAUGAAAUGAGUGUUCUUGAAUUAGAAAUUCUGUGGGAUCAAUCUUUGAUGGUGAGGGUUUUAGAAAGGAAAAAUAUAGUAAAAUGUGUAAUUUGUCUUAAUAAAAUCUAUCUCUACAUCUA